AUCACUUACAGGGCCCGGGGCUGCCGGACCUGCCAACGUGAAUCUUAUCGCCAUGGACCUUACCUUGCACAACCCAAAGUAGCUGCCUUGGGGCAGGGGGUGGCCAGAGUGCUUAGGGAAAUGUGGAGCCCUACCCAGAACAACGGUGGAGGGAAAGGGAAGAAACGCAGAAGUGCCCCAGUUCGGACGUAGGGAAGUCUUCCUCUUCGUGGUUUUUGGAGAACCCUAGCUAAGAGAGGAAAGGGACUUAUUGAAAGACCCGCAAGAAGGGACGGAAGUCUCAUAGCCCUGAGAGCUAGCUAAAGAGCACGGAUUGGUGCAUUUUACAAACCUCUAGCUACAGAAAAGUUCUCCAAGUCUGCACUCGACCCAGGAAGUCCAUCUGGCUUCACCUCUCACUUCAACUUGGGUACAGCCUUCUGGCGGGCAGGAGGAUGGCCUUUGGUGCGAACACUGCCGGAGUCCAGGGGGCUGGCUCCCUCACCUUUCAUCUUCUCCCGGCACUUGCAGGAUCCCUUUGUGGCCUUCCACAUCAACAAGGGCCUUGUGAAGAAGUAUAUGAACUCUCUCCUGAUUGGAGAACUGUCUCCAGAGCAGCCCAGCUUUGAGCCCACCAAGAAUAAAGAGCUGACAGAUGAGUUCCGGGAGCUGCGGGCCACAGUGGAGCGGAUGGGGCUCAUGAAGGCCAACCAUGUCUUCUUCCUGCUGUACCUGCUGCACAUCUUGCUGCUGGAUGGUGCAGCCUGGCUCACCCUUUGGGUCUUUGGGACGUCCUUUUUGCCCUUCCUCCUCUGUGCGGUGCUGCUCAGUGCAGUUCAGGCCCAGGCUGGCUGGCUGCAGCAUGACUUUGGGCACCUGUCGGUCUUCAGCACCUCAAAGUGGAACCAUCUGCUACAUCAUUUUGUGAUUGGCCACCUGAAGGGGGCCCCCGCCAGUUGGUGGAACCACAUGCACUUCCAGCACCAUGCCAAGCCCAACUGCUUCCGCAAAGACCCAGACAUCAACAUGCAUCCCUUCUUCUUUGCCUUGGGGAAGAUCCUCUCUGUGGAGCUUGGGAAACAGAAGAAAAAAUAUAUGCCGUACAACCACCAGCACAAAUACUUCUUCCUAAUUGGGCCCCCAGCCUUGCUGCCUCUCUACUUCCAGUGGUAUAUUUUCUAUUUUGUUAUCCAGCGAAAGAAGUGGGUGGACUUGGCCUGGAUGAUUACCUUCUACGUCCGCUUCUUCCUCACUUAUGUGCCACUAUUGGGGCUGAAAGCCUUCCUGGGCCUUUUCUUCAUAGUCAGGUUCCUGGAAAGCAACUGGUUUGUGUGGGUGACACAGAUGAACCAUAUUCCCAUGCACAUUGAUCAUGACCGGAACAUGGACUGGGUUUCCACCCAGCUCCAGGCCACAUGCAAUGUCCACAAGUCUGCCUUCAAUGACUGGUUCAGUGGACACCUCAACUUCCAGAUUGAGCACCAUCUUUUUCCCACGAUGCCUCGACACAAUUACCACAAAGUGGCUCCCCUGGUGCAGUCCUUGUGUGCCAAGCAUGGCAUAGAGUACCAGUCCAAGCCCCUGCUGUCAGCCUUCGCCGACAUCAUCCACUCACUAAAGGAGUCAGGGCAGCUCUGGCUAGAUGCCUAUCUUCACCAAUAACAACAGCCACCCUGCCCAGUCUGGAAGAAGAGGAGGAAGACUCUGGAGCCAAGGCAGAGGGGAGCUUGAGGGACAAUGCCACUAUAGUUUAAUACUCAGAGGGGGUUGGGUUUGGGGACAUAAAGCCUCUGACUCAAACUCCUCCCUUUUAUCUUCUAGCCACAGUUCUAAGACCCAAAGUGGGGGGUGGACACAGAAGUCCCUAGGAGGGAAGGAGCUGUUGGGGCAGGGGUGUAAAUUAUUUCCUUUUUCUAGUUUGGCACAUGCAGGUAGUUGGUGAACAGAGAGAACCAGGAGGGUAACAGAAGAGGAGGGACCUACUGAACCCAGAGUCAGGAAGAGAUUUAACACUAAAAUUCCACUCAUGCCGGGCGUGGUGGCACGCGCCUGUAAUCCCAGCUACCCAGGAGGCUGAGGCAGGAGAAUCGCUUGAACCGGGGAGGUGGAGGUUGCAGUGAGCUGAGAUCACGCCAUUGUACUCCAGCCUGGGCGACAGAGCAAGACUCCAUUUCAAAAAAAAAAAAAAAAUCCACUCAUAUAAAAGGUGAGCUCAGCUCACUGGUCCAUUUCUCAGUGGCUUCUCCAUCCUCAUUUGCAAACCUCAGAGGGAUAAGGCAGUUGAACCUGAUGAGCAAGAAUUAUAACAGCAAGGAAACAUUAAUGCUUAGAAUUCUGAGAUCCAGCACAACUCAGUCUGUGGGAGCUCAGCUCGCUGCCCAGGGAUAGGUAUGACCUAUGUCUGCCUUAGGCUGCUGGGAGAUGCCAUUCUCCAGUUUCAGAAGCAGGCAGGGCAAAGGUCAAGACUGUGGUAUUGGGGUCUUUUGGCUCUGAAGGAUCCUGGAACCACUGAUUUUGGUUUAUUCCCUCCAGGGUCUAAAGAGAACAAGAGGUGCUAGCUCUUACCAAAACAGAUGGUAGAGAGAGUUGCUGGCUAUUUAAAAAGCUCUUUCAUCUUUUAAUUCACCUCUUCUUUUCACCUCUUUAACCACUCCUCAGGAACAGAACACUUCUAGGACUGGGGGUCUUUUAGCUCCAUAAGCAAGUGAGCAGAUGGGACAAGUUAGUCUUUUCUCCCUAGAAACAAAGGGGAUGCCCAGUGGUUUCCCUUUGCUUCCCAACCUAAAAUUUCAAGUUUAAUAAAAUAGCAAUUAGCAGAAGUGACCAAAUUGGGAGAUAAUUAUCAGUCAUGAGGAAAGACACAGAUUUCGGUCAUAAAGAAUGUAAGGGCUAUAAGUAGAAACUUUCUAUAACCUAAAUGAUGUUAUAGAAUUAUUUUUGAGCAGGAGCAGAAAGAUUAAAUAUGAUCACUUCAUACUUCUAAAUCAGAAAUAGGAAGAUUAAAACCACAGAACAGUUUGUGAUUUCUAUUGCUGUAGCUAGGUAUCUUACUCUGUCCACUCUUGUUCAAGUAUCUAACUCUUCUGGAAACCAAAUAGGCUUUAGAAGAGAUUAUCCUAUAUUCCUAUCAGUAUAAUACUAAAAUGUAACUUUUUAAUCAUCUGGUUUUUAAAAGAUAAACAGUUUAGCCCAUCUCUCCAGAGAGCAAACAUAGGAAUAUGACUCAGGAGCCUCCUAGGGCUUAUCAUCAGCCCUCACACCCGCUUCCCCCUCCAACCCACAGCCUUUGCUUCCAGGUGGCAGGAUUACUACUUUGCCUCUUCAGCAGCAUCUACUCUAGGCAUAUUGAUCAUUUUAGACACUGGGAGAAGAGAACCUCAAACUAGGAGGAAAAGACAGAGCCUCCACUUAGUUUUGGGAGGGGAUGGCAGACAGUCAAGGAGAUGAGCGUCCUAAGGCAUGUUGGGAUAGGGUCAGAUGCACCACCCAUGGAGAGGUUUGUCAACACAAAGACAUGGAAGGUUAGAGGUUUGUCAACAAAAAGACAUGGAAGGUUAGGUUUGUCAACACAAAGACAUGGAAGAUUAGAGGUUUGUCAACACAAAGACACAGGAAGAAUGGGCUGCAGAAGAUUUAGAUGUUUUCCAUUUGGGCACAUUUUACUUAGCUGGAGAACUAGGUUUAAAACAGCCUGGGUAGGAAAAUUAGAAGCAAGCUGGAUGCAGUGGCUCAUGCCUGUAAUCCCAACACUUUUGGGAGGUCCAGGCAGGAGGAUCACUUGGGCCCAGGAGGUCAAGCCUGCAGCGAGCUGAGAUCACACCACUGCACUCCAGCCUGGGGUGAUAGAACAAGACCCUGUCUCAAAAAAAAAAAAAACAACAAAAACUUAGAAUUGAGGAGUUGUACCUCCAUUGGCUUCCUCACUCCAAAAUAGGUGCUGAUCCUUCCUAUUCCUAUUCUUUGCCACCUUUUGGGUGUGGUGUCACCAGCCUGUUUAGCCAAGUAGCUUUGGGCAUAGGCUGCCCAAUCUGAGCAAACACCAGUGAGGCUCUAUUGAGCCAAGACCAAGUCCUCAAAGCACCUGAACCACUGUGGCCUUCUCAGCCUACAGCAGUGUGGUCUCUUACAUGGCCACAAAGGGACACACAGUGACAAAAGGCUCGGAAUGUUACAAUGGUAAAAUGAGUGAUCUCAAAUCCACUGACAGAUAUAAAAUAGGCUUAGAGAGGAAAAGCUGCCUCUGGUCAAGUAGAUCAUGGCAGCAUGAAUUCCAACUCACUUUUUUACAACUCCAACUUCUAUGUUUAUCUUUGUUACUUUCACUUUUUUACAACCUGGCCAGAGGCAUUUUUUAAAUCAGGCCCAAUAUCAGUAUUCUUUUUGUGUGUGCCAAUUUUGUUAUCACAUCCCUAUGAAGUUGAAAAAUAAAGUUAAUUUUGACCAAAA